CCCUCACGCUGGCCUGUUGAGGCCCAGUUCAUGCCUCUGUUGGCUUCUCCAGGCCCAGCCCCUGCCUGUUGGCGGCCUCUAGAGGCCCAGCCUCUACCUCAACAGUGGGCCCUCCACGCCCACCUGUUGCCUUGCCGUGGCGUCCUCGGGCCAGGCUCCCGCCUUGGGGCGGCCCCCGCAGGCCCAGCUCCUGCCUCACGGCCCUCCGGAGGCCAAGCUCAUGCGUCAGAGCGGCCUCUCCCGGCCUGGCGUUUGCUCCUUUGCAUGGGCUCCAGGUCCUGCACUUCCUCCAGUCGGCCUCUCCAGGCCCAGCGCUUCCUCCCGGCAGCCUCUGCAGGACCAGACUGUCGUCAAGUAGGCCUGUCCAGGGACAGCUCCUGCCUCCCGGCAGACUCUGCAGGCCCAAGUCGUCCUCAAGUCAGCCUCCCCAGGCCCAGCUCCGGCCUCUCGGCGGCCUCUCCAGGUGCAAAAGUUCCUCGAGUCCGUCUCUCCAGGUCCAGCUCCUCCUGUCUCCCAGUGGCCUCUUUCAGCCCAGCCCAGCUCAUGCCUCCCGGCGACCUUCCCAGGCCCCGCUUUUGA